GUGGUGAUGAUGGUGUUGGAGGAGGUGAUGGUAGUGAUGGUAAUGGAAGAAGUGGAGGCAGUGGUGGCGGUAGGGGUGGUGGUGGUUGUUGAAGAUAAUGCUGCCAUGCUCUAUGGAUCUAAAUUCUAUACUUGACCUAUCUAAACGCUGUGAUAGAUUUCAGAAGUGAGCAGAGAGGGAGAGCACUUAGGUCCUGGGACUUAAUGAACACAGGUGCACAGAGAGCAUUGGUACUGGUCUCUGCCCAUAAACAUCACAUGUGCCUUUUGAAGUGAUUCUUCUGUUUGGGACAGUGCAGGCAAAACAUACAUGCUCAGGCAGAUACACAGUGUUCUACUGGUUGUGAAAUUUUUGGUGUUUGUUUGUUGGGGUUUUUUAUUUCUUAAAUUUUAAUUUAUUUUUGUUUUUUAUUCCUCCAAAGUUUGAAGCCUUAUUUUGAGAAUACAGGAAUCAGGUCUGUGGAAAGAAGGAAAAGUUGAAAUAGCUAAAAAGAAAGCAGGGCUGAAAGUGGUGGACACAGAUGAGGGGACACAAUACAGGGAGAUGACAAAGGGGAAAAGCAUCCUCACACACACGAGACCAAACUGUGGUUUAGGCAGAGCUUAAAAGUAACUGCCAAUGCACAACCACACAGGAUAGGUACGUGGCCCUGGGACAAAAGGUGAGAGCUGGAGCCAGGCCUGGUGGCUGCGGCACAGAGGGAGCUGUGGCAGUCAGUCUAGCGCCCACCUUCCCGGGGACAAAAGGCGACACUCUCUAGACCAGACAAGGCAGAAAGAGUCCCUGGAGGGCCUUUGAGGUGCAGCUUCCUUUACAGACAGAGGCCUGCUGCCAGAAACUCGGCUGAUUCACAAAGAAAGAAGUGAAAUGCUAACAAAUGGUUUCCAUUAUCACCGUGCAGUCUCCACCCUCAUUCUGUAUGUGUGCUGUGUUUUUUUCUUUCUUUUUUUCAUCUUUUCAUGGGUUGUAACUAAACAAUGAGGUGAUUGCCAUCCCAGUGGAUUGCACAACAUAACCAGCGGCUGGGCUGGAGCAUAGCCUUCUCCAAGGAAAUUCUGGACAAGAAAAAUGAACAAGCUGGAAGUAAGGAGGAUGUCUGUUUUGCACAACACCUAUGUACACUUUUAGUGCUCAUAAAGAAGGUGGAACGAGGGUCUUAGAUUCUUAGUUCCUCUGUGGCGCACCUGUCAGCCCACCAGUGUGGCACUCUCCUUCUUAAAUAAAACACUACAUAGCCAAAGUGAAAGGGAGGCUCACCCAGUUAUCCAAGAAGGUGAAUUGGGACCACUUGUUAUUUCCCAGUAUAACAUGAAAUAAUGAUUUACUUGGGUUGAAUAAACUGGCGCAGCUGUGGGAAGAGUCUUCAAUUCCUUUCAAUAAACAUUCAUUAAGUGCCUACACUGGGACAGCCCCACGGAUAGAAAUACUCCUAAGACCUCAAGAAGUUAAUCCAGCAGAUGCCUAAACUUGUCCCAAAUCCCUGGAUAACCAAGUAUAAAUUUGAUCAUGAGGAUACCAUCCAUGUUGUAUUCUCCUUGUGAUUCACUUUUUCUGCAAGGCAGCAAUUACUUAAGCAAAGAUGCUAUUAACUUUACAGUGCCUGGCAAGUUUUCGUGAUAGCUAAACAUUGCAGCACCCUGAUGAACACAGCCAUAGCUGGAGCAGCUUCCUCCCUCUGACUGCGACAUGGCUGAAGAAAAUGGAUAUUUCAAAAACAAACGUUUCAGUUUGUUACUCAGCAUCUUUGUUGGCAAAUGAUUGCAGAUAAUCGCCCCACAGCUGCAGGCUGAGCGUUCUACAAUUGCUCAGUUCCACUGAGCAUGUGCAUGGCCAGCCAUUCCAAUCACGACUGGGACACAAAGCGGCGAUUUCUUCCUGCCAGAGAGGGCCAGAUGGGGGCAUGGGAUGAACAGGAGGCAUCACUUUCUCUUCUGCACCCAGAUCUGCCAGUAACUAGCUGCCUGAUUCUGGCCAAAUGUCUUUAAUGAUAUUAAUAAGAAUAGCUGAUAUUUAUGUAGCACCAACUAGAUGCCAGGCACUGUGCUAAAUGCUCAUUCAAUUUAACCCUCUCAAUAAUCCAAUAUGGAGGGUAUAACGUUUUGAUUUUUGAAAGAAGAUGUUGAGGGGCAGAGAGGUUAAGUCUCUUGCUAAAGAUUGAGAAGUGCGGUGAUUGUGUGGUGAUUGAGAAGGAAAAAUGUCUGCCCUCAUCUCUGGAAUUUCUAAUUACUCACAAUGUUCUGGGUCUCUAGAGACAGAUGCUCUCUGUGGGUCUCUCGUUAGCUCCAGAGUAAAUUUCCCCAAUGCAGACUUUUUAUUUUGUUCAUGUUGUCAUUAUCAAAUCAACCUUAAAAGAAGAAACACUAAAAGACUGGGAAUAUUCUGAAAUAUAAUUAUAUGAGAACCAAGUGACUUUAGAAAGGACAGCAGGUUUUCAUCUCUCCUGACCUUUCCUCCUGAGAUAAUGAAAGAGCUAGAUGAAACUCCUUAACAUAAGCUCGAAAAUCCCUGUCAAAUAGCCCUUCAUUAGAGUUAACCACCCUGAUGGCAUUCCAGCAUUCCCCAUAAGUCAUAUGUGUUACUGCAUAAUAGGAGCCCAUGUGGGACUAAGAUAGUUAAAGCCAUGCACAGGAAGUAGCUAAAACAGCACAAAGCCCCCUGACAAACACACUCAUGGAAGUAAAUUCUUCAUUUCCAGCUCUUCGCCUCAGGUUACCUAGGAUUUGCAUGUGCUGCAUGCCUGGGCAAAGCUGGGCUGAGUUAUCUCUUUCAUGCCUUGAGUCAGAUUUUCUGGGUGUGAAGUCAGCAGACAAGCCAGGAAAUGUCACUGCAGAAGAGCAAGGGAGCUCAAGACGCGAUGGCAGCUGUCACUCCAGAGUGGUGUGGAGUGGGACGGUAUCUGAUGUGUCCUCAGAUUCGGUUUCCCUUGGGAUGUGUUUGGUGCUGACUGCUUGUGAUCCAUGUUUUCUUGGAUGCAGGUUGGUAGAGGUGCAGCAAUUUUUGCAGUGAAACUGAAGUCCAGCUGCUCAAACAGAAAUGGCCUCAUCUAAUGGACACUUUAAUGAAGUUUUGGCCAGUGGUCGUGCAGUCCAAGGGGCUGGAUGGCAUGCUGGACCCAAGCUCAGCUCAGCGUCCGGACCCAAUAACAGUUUUACCAAGGGAGCAGCUUUCUAUCCUGGCCACACUGAGGUGCAUAGCGUAAUGUCCAUGUUGUUCUACACUCUGAUCACAGCUUUUCUGAUCGGCAUACAGGCGGAACCACACUCAGAGAGCAAUGUCCCUGCAGGACACACCAUCCCCCAAGCCCACUGGACUAAACUUCAGCAUUCCCUUGACACUGCCCUUCGCAGAGCCCGCAGCGCCCCGGCAGCGGCGAUAGCUGCACGCGUGGCGGGGCAGACCCGCAACAUUACUGUGGACCCCAGGCUGUUUAAAAAGCGGCGACUCCGUUCACCCCGUGUGCUGUUUAGCACCCAGCCUCCCCGUGAAGCUGCAGACACUCAGGAUCUGGACUUCGAGGUCGGUGGUGCUGCCCCCUUCAACAGGACUCACAGGAGCAAGCGGUCAUCAUCCCAUCCCAUCUUCCACAGGGGCGAAUUCUCGGUGUGUGACAGUGUCAGCGUGUGGGUUGGGGAUAAGACCACCGCCACAGACAUCAAGGGCAAGGAGGUGAUGGUGUUGGGAGAGGUGAACAUUAACAACAGUGUAUUCAAACAGUACUUUUUUGAGACCAAGUGCCGGGACCCAAAUCCCGUUGACAGCGGGUGCCGGGGCAUUGACUCAAAGCACUGGAACUCAUAUUGUACCACGACUCACACCUUUGUCAAGGCGCUGACCAUGGAUGGCAAGCAGGCUGCCUGGCGGUUUAUCCGGAUAGAUACGGCCUGUGUGUGUGUGCUCAGCAGGAAGGCUGUGAGAAGAGCCUGACCUGCCGACACGCUCCCUCCCCCUGCCCCUUCUACACUCUCCUGGGCCCCUCCCUACCUCAACCUGUAAAUUAUUUUAAAUUAUAAGGACUGCAUGGUAAUUUAUAGUUUAUACAGUUUUAAAGAAUCAUUAUUUAUUAAAUUUUUGGAAGCA